UGCAGCAGGUGGCGGAGCCCCGCCCCCUUCUCCCCGCGCACCAAUAGGAACCAGACCUGAAGAGGACGAACCAAGAACGAAAAGAACCACCCACUCGGGAGCCGCAACCUAGAAGCCAGAGUUGUGUAUCAGAUUCAACUAGGAGAAAAUCCCACCUCCAGGCUCCAUUAAUCCUUCCAAUGGAGUGGAAGUUUCUCUCACAGAGAAACUAGUAAGGGGAUCCAAUGGGAAAAGAACGUUCACACGGACUAGAAGACGAAACCAAUGGAAUGGAAAAUUGUCCUCGCGUUGGUAGAAGCAGCCAAUGAGAUGAAAAGAGCCCGCCUCCAAAGUGGCUGCAGAGGCAAUGGGGUCCGAGGAGCUGCAGGUGUGACUGAUGGGAAUGAAGUGGCCAAGGCCCAGCAGGCAACUCCUGGGGGAGCAGCCCCAACCAUCUUCUCCCGGAUCCUGGACAAGAGCCUCCCAGCUGACAUUCUCUAUGAGGACCAGCAGUGUCUUGUGUUCCGUGAUGUGGCCCCUCAGGCUCCUGUGCACUUCCUGGUCAUUCCUAAGAAGCCCAUUCCUCGGAUUAGCCAGGCUGAAGAAGAAGACCAGCAGCUUCUAGGACACCUACUCCUUGUGGCCAAGCAGACAGCAAAGGCUGAGGGCCUGGGAGAUGGAUACCGACUUGCUCAAUUUCAGUGAUCAACGAUGGGAAGCUGGGUGCACAAUCUGUGUAUCAUCUGCACAUUCAUGUACUUGGGGGCCGGCAGCUCCAGUGGCCUCCAGGUUGAACCUGCCAACUGAUUAAAGGACACCAGACUCUGGAUGCUUGGAUGGAAAGGGAAAAAUGGACCCUGUGAUGCUAAUAAAACUGUUCUCCCUUAA